ACUUCCGGGGUCGAGGCGAGGCCAACGAUACGCCUGCUGCAGCAGGAGGAGUUACGAGCCGGGCCGCGCGCUGCCUAAAUACCUAAACCAGGUUUAGCGCCUGCUCAUAUAAAGCUCUCCUAACUCGUCUUCCGGUGGGAAUUUCUUCACGUGGGCCGGAGUCGGAGACUGAGUUUAGCUUUACUGAGGAGCUCUAAAUUUAGGCGGGUAUGAGUGAUUUCAGUGAAGAAUUAAAAGGGCCUGUGACAGAUGAUGAAGAAGUGGAAACAUCUGUGCUCAGUGGUGCAGGAAUGCAUUUUCCUUGGCUUCAAACAUACGUAGAAACUGUGGCCAUUGGAGGGAAAAGGAGGAAGGAUUUUGCUCAGACAACAAGUGCUUGUUUAAGUUUUAUCCAAGAAGCUCUGCUGAAGCACCAAUGGCAGCAAGCUGCAGAAUACAUGUACAGUUAUUUUCAGACCUUGGAAGAUUCAGAUAGCUACAAAAGGCAGGCUGCACCUGAGAUUAUUUGGAAGCUCGGAAGUGAAAUUCUAUUUUAUCAUCCCAAAAGCAACAUGGAGAGUUUCAAUACUUUUGCUAACCGGAUGAAAAAUAUUGGCGUCAUGAAUUAUUUAAAGAUCUCCUUACAACAUGCAUUAUACCUUCUGCAUCAUGGAAUGCUUAAAGAUGCUAAGAGAAAUCUGAGUGAGGCAGAGACAUGGAGACAUGGUGAAAAUACGUCUUCCCGGGAAAUAUUAAUCAACCUUAUUCAGGCCUAUAAAGGGCUUUUACAGUAUUAUACCUGGUCUGAAAAGAAGAUGGAAUUGUCAAAGCUUGAUAAGGAUGAUUAUGCUUACAAUGCAGUAGCCCAGGAUGUGUUCAACCACAGCUGGAAGACAUCUGCAAAUAUUUCUGCAUUGAUUAAAAUUCCUGGAGUUUGGGACCCUUUUGUGAAGAGUUAUGUAGAAAUGCUGGAAUUCUAUGGGGAUCGAGAUGGAGCCCAAGAGGUACUCACCAAUUAUGCAUAUGAUGAAAAGUUUCCAUCAAAUCCAAAUGCCCAUAUCUACUUAUACAACUUUCUAAAGAGACAGAAGGCACCAAGAUCAAAAUUGAUAAGUGUGCUUAAGCAUCUACAGAAAAUUUCAAUAAUGUACAGUACACUGAGAUAAACAGAGAAAGUUGGCUCCAGCUGCCAUCUCCAUGUAUGUAUCAUCCACACUAUCCCCUGCUGCCCGGAUGAGACUGAGGAGAGAGGAUCAGAAGUCUUGUGCAACCCUGGUUGGAAUACUCUGCACUGAUAUUUUUUGAAAAUCAACUUUAUUGAAAUUUAGUUUUCAGAGAGUAAACACACUUAUUUUAAGUAUGUGCUUGGAUGCGUUACAUUCAUGAACCACCAUGGUAAUCAUGAUAUAGAACAUUUCUGUCGCCCCCAGAAUGCCUUUCAUUUCCCUUUGCAGCCUGUCUGUCCCCACAACCAUGGCCCCAGACAAUCACUGAUCUGCUUAUUGUCACUAUAGAUUAAUUUUUAUCUCUUCUAGAAUUUCAUGUAAAUGGACUCUUAUGUAGUCAUUUUAAUCUGGCUUCUCUUGCUCAGCGUAACAUAUUUGAGAUUCACCCAUGUUAUUGUGUAUAUUAGUAAUUUCCUUAUUACUGCUGAAUAGUAUUUCAUUUUUAUACAUUCACUUCUUGAUGGACAUUUGGGUAAUUUUUACUUUUUGGCUAUUGUGAAUGAUGCUGCUGAGAACAUUCAUGUACAAGAUUCUGUAUACACAUAUAUUUUCAUGUUUCUUGGGUAGCUACCUGAGAGAGGAGUUGCUGCCUAAGAGUAGUAAGGAAAGUAUAUGCUUAACUUCCUAAGAAACUGCCCAGCUGUUUUUUGAAGUGACUGUACCAUCGACAUUCACACAGCAAUAUGAAAAUUCAGUUUCUCCACAUCUGUGCCAACACUUGGUAUUGGAGGUCUUUUGAAUAAUAGCCUCUUGUGGGUGUCCCAUGUGGCAUUAAAUUGUAUUUCCCUAAUGACUAGUGAUGUUGAGCAUCUUUUAGUAUGUCUAUUGGCCAUCCUGUAUCUUCUUUUGUCAUGUGUCCAACUACUUAGUCUAUUUUUGGGGGGAUCAAUUGUCUUCUUACUGAUUUGGAAAUUUUUAUAUAAUCUGGAUAUAAGUCCUUUGUGAAGAAUAUUAAUUAUGAAUAUUUUCUCUCUGACUGUGCCUUGCCUUUUGGUUUCCUUAAUAGUAUCUUUCAAAGAGUAGAAACUUCUAGUUUUGAUGUUCAGUUUGUACAUUUUUUUUUCUUUUAUGGUUAGUGCUUUUUGUCUAAGAAAUAUUUGCCUAUCUCAAGAUAAUGAAGAGUUCUUUUUUUUUUUUUUUUCUAGAUGUGUUGUAUAGUUUUAUGUUUAGGUCAUGGUAGAUUUUUAGCUAUUUUUUUGUGGGUAGUGUGUGGCAAAGGUCAAGGUUCAUUUUUUCCCAUGUGGUUGUUCCAGCAUUAUAUUGAAGACUCUCCUUUCUCCAUUUAGUACAUUUGGAACUUUGUUGAAAACCAGUAGGCUGUAUAUGAAGUCUGUUGUGUUCUAGUGAUGUAUAUUUCCACCUCAAUAGAUGAAAAUUCAGUUUCUCCACAUCCUUGCCAAUACUUCAUAUUGUAGGUCUUCUAAAUGUGAGUUAUUGCCAUUCUAGUGGGUGUGUAGUAAUAUCUCAUGUGGCCUUAAUAUGGUUACUGUAGCUUUGUAGCAAGUCUUGGAAUCAUAUCAUGAAAGUCAUACAAAUUUGUUCUUUUUCAAAAUUGCUUUUGGCUUUUCUAGGUUCUUUAACUUUCCAUGUAUAUUGUAUAAUCAACUUACCUGUUGCUACAAAAAGGUCUUGCUGAGAUUUUGAAUCUAUAGAUCAGUUUGAGAGAAUUGACAUCUCAACUGUAUUGAGGUUUCCAAAGUGUAAACAUGGCAUGUCUCUCCAUUUAUUUAGGUUUUUAAUUUCUCUCUGAACUGUUUUGUAGUUUUUAGUGUAUGUAUUUUGUUAAAUUUGUCCCUAAGUGUUUCAUGGGGUUGUUGUAUAUAAUAUUGCUUAACAUUUUAAAUUGUGGGAAAAUAUAUACAAAAAUAAAUGUUACCAUUUUGAUCAUUUUUAAAGCA